GGCAGUGUCUGCCCCUUGCAAUGCUUGGAUUUCCUUCCUCAAAAGGCAGCCUUCGAUGAUCUGAAAUUCAAGUUCCAGCAGGCAUCCUGUACUGUAUCUGUCAGCCCUGCCACCCGAGUGGUCUGAAAGCCCUGGAAGAGACCGCGGUUAUCACAGGAGAACACUUUCCAUGGGGAGCACGCAGCAAGCUCCAGAAUAAGCGCUUAAAAUCCGCGUCUCAGUCAACACUGCAAACCUUCCAACAAAGUCUUACACCGAAAAGGACCCUGCUGAGCUGAGGGCUGAAGCCCCAGGUCCUGGGACCCUUGGAAACAGCCCGCGGGCCAGGAGCUGCUGUGGACCGUGAAGGUGUAGGGCCUAGGCACUUCCCAAGCAAGACACGAUGCUCCCGCAGAGGAAUCUUCCCGGGAGCAAGCCAGGAGUCCUGGGCUCAAAAUCACCCUCGGCAAGACCAAGGCCUCUGAGCGAGCCACUGCCUGCCCAUCGCUUCCUUCUUGUCACAUGGAAAGGGAAACUCACCGCGGGGCCAGUGUUUACUGAGGGGCCGCUUCCAUCACAGACCUGACAGCACAUUCGAGAAAAGUGCGAGGAAAACAGGAGUUAUUUAUAAAAAUGUAAAGCAGAAGAGAAUACUGGGACCAGUGGCACAAGCAGGAACCAGGAAGUGACAGUGUGCCCAGCCUCUCACCUGACCCUGGACAGGGAUAUAAAGAGCCCGGGCUCAGGGGGCUCCACACCUGCACCUCCCUCUCACCUGCUCCUCUACCUGCUCCACCCUCAAUCCACCAGAACCAUGGGCUGCUGUGGCUGCUCCGGAGGCUGUGGCUCCGGCUGUGGAGGCCUUGGCUCCGGCUGUGGGGGCUGUGGCUCCGGCUGUGGAGGCCGUGGCUCCGGCUGUGGGGGCUGUGGCUCCGGCUGUGGAGGCUGUGGCUCCGGCUGUGGGGGCUGUGGCUCCGGCUGUGGGGGCUGUGGGGGAUGUGGCUCCGGCUGCUGUGUGCCUGUCUGCUGCUGCAAGCCCAUGUGCUGCUGUGUGCCAGCUUGUUCCUGCUCCAGCUGUGGCAAAGGGGGCUGUGGCUCUUGCGGGGGCUCCAAGAGAGGCUGUGUCUCCUGUGGGGUGUCCAAGGGGGCCUGUGGCUCCUGUGGGGGGUCCAAGGGGGGCUGUGGCUCCUGUGGGGGGUCCAAGGGGGGCUGUGGCUCCUGUGGGGGGUCCAAGGGGGGCUGUGGUUCUUAUGGCUGCUCCCAGUGCAGCUGCUGUAAGCCCUGCUGCUGCUCCUCAGGCUGUGGGUCAUCCUGCUGCCAGUCCAGCUGCUGUAAGCCUUACUGCUGCCAGUCCAGCUGCUGUAAGCCCUGUAGCUGCUUCUCAGGCUGUGGAUCAUCCUGCUGCCAAUCCAGCUGCUACAAGCCCUGCUGCUGCCAGUCCAGCUGCUGUGUCCCCGUGUGCUGCCAGUGUAAGAUCUGAGGCUCUGACUGCAGACUGCAGGUGGCCUGACUGGUGAAGGGCCCGUCUGCCCAGCUUCCUUGCCCUGGGUUCUCUGGUGCUCCACUGUCUCCACUGUGUCCUCACUGGCUUCAUCCACUCCACACCAGUGCUUCCGAAACUGACUGAGGACCCCUUCUGGCUCAUUGCCUACUACUUCUCCUGAACUUCCUCUCCCUGCUCCUCACUCAUUUAAGAUCCAAAGCGGCCCACUGAGGCCCCAGAGGCAGAUCAGACCCCUUAGACCCUGACAGCUGCUCCUUCUUUCAGGAGUGUGAUCGACCCUCAAUCUCUCUGGCUGUCUGUAUAUCAAGACUGAAUCCUGACCCUCUAAAUAAACAAAGUCUCUAAGCACAAA